CGAGUCCCGGCCAGUGCCUCUGCUUCCGGCUCGAAUUGCUCUCGCUCACGCUUGCCUUCAACAUGUCCGAGACUGCGCCUGCCGCGCCCGCUGCUCCGGCCCCUGCCGAGAAGACUCCCGUGAAGAAGAAGGCCCGCAAGUCUGCAGGUGCGGCCAAGCGCAAAGCGUCUGGGCCCCCGGUGUCCGAGCUCAUUACUAAAGCUGUUGCCGCCUCCAAGGAGCGCAGCGGCGUAUCUUUGGCCGCUCUCAAGAAAGCGCUGGCAGCCGCUGGCUAUGACGUGGAGAAGAACAACAGCCGCAUCAAGCUGGGUCUCAAGAGCCUGGUGAGCAAGGGCACCCUGGUGCAGACCAAGGGCACCGGCGCGUCGGGUUCCUUCAAACUCAACAAGAAGGCGGCCUCUGGGGAAGCCAAGCCUAAGGCUAAAAAGGCAGGCGCGGCCAAGGCCAAGAAGCCAGCAGGAGCGGCGAAGAAGCCCAAGAAGGCGACGGGGGCGGCCACCCCCAAGAAGAGCGCCAAGAAGACCCCAAAGAAGGCGAAGAAGCCGGCUGCAGCUGCUGGAGCCAAAAAAGCGAAAAGCCCGAAAAAGGCGAAAGCAGCCAAGCCAAAAAAGGCGCCCAAGAGCCCAGCGAAGGCCAAAGCAGUUAAACCCAAGGCGGCUAAACCAAAGACCGCCAAGCCCAAGGCAGCCAAGCCAAAGAAGGCGGCAGCCAAGAAAAAGUAGAAAGUUCCUUUGGCCAACUGCUUAGAAGCCCAACACAACCCAAAGGCUCUUUUCAGAGCCACCCA